AUCCAGGAAGUGAAAUCGACGUCGGGGUCAAUGAAAACAAACGGGGAGCCCAGGGGGAAGGAAGGCAGGCGAGGAAGAGGCAGCGCCGGGGCGCCGGAGGGAGCAGCCGGGCUGCGGAAGCGCGAGCAGGAGGCCGGUCGCGGGCGCAUUUUUGCCGUUGUCGCGGCCGCCGCCGCCGAGGCUUACCCGGGAAUGUCUGGGCCCGCGCCUCGCGGCCCCCAAGCUCCACGCUGCGCCCGCUGUCCCGGCCUCUAAAGGCCGCCACGUCCCUGCGGCGCGCGCAGGCAGAAAGCGGCUUCGUGCCGGCGGAGGGGGCCCGGGCGGGCCGGGAGGGGCUGCCCCAGGCCCUGCGCCUACCCCAUCACCGCGGCCGGCGCCGGGCCGGGAGGAUGCGCGGUGUGGGGCUCUGAAGCAUGGAGGGGGUGUUGUACAAGUGGACCAACUAUCUCACAGGCUGGCAGCCUCGUUGGUUUGUUUUAGAUAAUGGAAUCUUAUCCUACUAUGAUUCACAAGAUGAUGUUUGCAAAGGGAGCAAAGGAAGCAUAAAGAUGGCAGUUUGUGAAAUUAAAGUUCAUUCAGCAGACAACACAAGAAUGGAAUUAAUCAUUCCUGGAGAGCAGCAUUUCUACAUGAAGGCAGUGAAUGCAGCUGAAAGACAGAGGUGGCUGGUCGCUCUGGGGAGCUCCAAAGCAUGUUUGACUGAUACAAGGACUAAAAAAGAAAAAGAAAUAAGUGAAACCAGUGAAUCGCUGAAAACCAAAAUGUCUGAACUUCGCCUCUACUGUGACCUCUUAAUGCAGCAAGUUCAUACAAUACAGGAAUUUGUUCACCAUGAUGAGAAUCAUUCAUCUCCUAGUGCAGAGAACAUGAAUGAAGCCUCUUCUCUGCUUAGUGCCACGUGUAACACAUUCAUCACAACGCUUGAGGAAUGUGUGAAGAUAGCCAAUGCCAAGUUUAAACCUGAGAUGUUUCAACUGCACCAUCCGGAUCCCUUAGUUUCUCCUGUGUCACCUUCUCCUGUUCAAAUGAUGAAGCGUUCUGUCAGCCACCCUGGUUCUUGCAGUUCAGAGAGGAGUAGCCACUCUAUAAAAGAACCAGUAUCUACACUUCACCGACUCUCCCAGCGACGCCGAAGAACCUACUCAGAUACAGAUUCUUGUAGUGAUAUUCCUCUUGAAGACCCAGAUAGACCUGUUCACUGUUCAAAAAAUACACUUAAUGGAGAUUUGGCAUCAGCAACCAUUCCUGAAGAAAGCAGACUUAUGGCCAAAAAACAAUCUGAAUCAGAAGAUACUCUUCCAUCCUUCUCUUCCUGAAGAAACUGAAGUGUCCAACUUCCUCUAAGUAUUGCUAUGCAAAAGCUGCUGUAAUUAAACUAUUGUUAUAGGGAGUAGUUUUUUCCCUUAGGACUCUGCACUUUAUAGAAUGUUGUAAAACAGACAAACAAGAAAACAAACCACAUACUUUUGAAGUGUAUUUUAUCUUUAUAUAGUUUGUUUGCAAGAGUAUUUUCCUAAUAACUUCACAGUAUGAAUGUGCAUCUUUUUUUUUUGAACAAAUGAUGGUGUAACAUUUUGACAUCCAUAAGGACAAAUGUAGAUAUUUUUCUUAAAAACUCUGAGGGGACUGACAGCAUGGUCAGGGUGUAUUGUAGCUUAUAAACAUGAAAUCUUAUAAGGUUUCAGUUUGACAGAAGUGUGAUAUAUGUAACUUGUGCCAUGGACCAAAUGGUCACUUUACCACAGCUAAAAAUGAGUUACGAUAGCAGCUUGAUGGUGAUUGUAUUGUAUUCCUUUAAUCAAAAAGGAAACACAAUAUUCUAAGUAUCUUUAGCCCAAAUACCAUGACAUAUUGAGCAUCUUUAAAUAACCAGACUGUAUUGUCCUUCAUAUGUGAAGUUGACACUACUGAUUUGUCAAUACCAAAUUUUGGGUUAAAGUGUUUAAUUUUUAUGUAUUUAUUUUCUUGUUGCCUCAAAAGAUGAUUGCAUUCUAACUUUUGUGACCUACCAAAUUUAAGAUGUGUAUACGUUGUUCUUUACGUUGUUCUAGAAAAGAGAUUUUAAUGCUGUAGUGACUUUGCUCACUUACACUAGAGAAAUAAACAACUUUCAAUGGAAGAGAAUUUUAGUGCUUUUUUUUUCCUAAAAUAGAUAUUAAGCUGCUGUUGUAAAGUAUUGUUUGCAGCUCUUUCCAAUAUCUAGAGACAUUUUUAUUUAUGAAUAUUUAUACAAAAAGGAAUUCUGUCAAGAUGACUGCUCUAUAUCACUUGAGAAUGGCAUUAUUUAAUUAAAGAACAAAUAGCAUUUUUUGGUAGUGCCUGUCCAUACCUAUUGUCAUUGUUUGCCUUGUAAUCUGUUUUUUUGAAUUCAUUUUGGGCUGAUAGUUUUGUUUAAGGUUUUGGAUAAGGAGCACUUUAAAACAAACUGGUGUGUUGUUUUUAAGUUAAUCAUAUGUUUAAUAAAUGCGUGGUUUUUGCAUUCAAACACAUCAUAUAAUACAUUGUAUUUUUUACAUUCAUUGAUAUUCUGUCUAAUCUUUAUUAGGCACUAAUAUAAUUCUAAUGGAUUUGAGUUUGUUUGUAUAUUUAGGCCUGCUGGUGAAGACACAAAUGAAGCAUAAUUUUUGUUGCCUGUGAGCUUAGAAUGGUGUGACCUAUUUCAUUUUAUUUCAAUUUAUCUUGUAAGUUUAUGUGGGAUAUUUUAAAAUAAUUAAUAUUUGGUAUUUGUUUAAAAAACUGUAAUUAUAGGCCUUCCAUCUUAAGUUUAAGAUGGACAUAAACAGUCUAUACAUUAAUAUGUGUUUGGGUAAACUGUAUGCUACUUGAAGUGUUUGUAAUUUUAAAUAACACACAGGUCAUCAGACUACUCUAUAUUCAGUGGAGUCUUUGCCUGCUCAUAAGUUGUACUUCAUAUGUCUAAUUUGAAAAAAAAAGUUUGAUAAUGUAGUAAGUUAUGACGUUGAGCAGGUAAUCAGGUUUUUCUUGUUUUUUUUUUUUUUUUAAAUUUUGUAGUAAGAACUUGCACAGUAUUAAGACCAUGAAGGUCAGGGUGCUAUUGAUUGGGAGUUUUUUCUGGUAGUGAGUUUUUUUGCAGUAAUAGGUUUAUAAGGAAAACACCGUAACAAGCUUUUGAACUUAUAGAAAAUAAUCACAUCCAUUUUCUAUUGCUUUACCCAAAUAGAUGGGUUCGUGAAGAGUUUUCUGUGAAUAUUUUAAAAAUACAAUGCAAUUAUUUCUGGUUUGUAUCAUUUUUUCCCCCUUAAAACAGGUCCUUGAACAGGUUUGCGGUAUCCCUAAGUAUGUCUUUUGUUAUGACUUGGAGCCACUUUUUGUUGUUAUUGUUAGGAACCAAACACAUCUGUGAAAUCAUUUUUUUUGUGGGAGUAUAAAUAUAUCUUGAAUUAUAUCCAGGUUUUGAUCAGUGAAUUAGUAGCAUGAAGAAACCUAUAAAGCUUAAGGGAACCUUGCAUUUUGAGGAGUCCUUUAUUUUCAAGUGUGCCUGACUUUUUUGAAUUUUAAGAAAAAGAUGAACCAUAUAACAAUUCUGUAAGAAUUUUAGCUUGUCAAGUUGUUCUAUACUUUAUAGAAAAAUUAUUGGUUAUUAUUAGUUAUUAGUAGUCCCUUUUUUUUGCUUUGUCUAGGUCAUGGGGUUAUUGAGAAACAUGAAAAGUUAUUGAGAAAUUUGGAGGUUCUCUUGGCAGCCUAUCAGUGAUCUUCUAAGCAAAAGCAGUGCUUGUUUUUCAUUUCAAGUGCUUGCUCACUAUUCUUUGGGAAUCGCAGGCCUCCAUGACUAAAGGGAUUUUGAUACAAUUCUUUUAUAAAUGAGCUGAAUUUGAAUUUUCUUACAUCAUAUGGGAUUAUUGCAUGAUCUUCAGUCAGGAAAAAUCCAGAAAUGGAUGCUAUUGCUUAAACUUAAAUUCCAAGGCAGAAGAUAGAGUAUCUUCAUUUCCACAGAUGCCCUAGAACCUUUGACCUUGAAUUGUAGUUUUUCAGUAUGUAUUAUCACAUUUAGAAAUGUAAAAAUCACAAGAUCUCAGGAAAUGCGCCCUUGUGAUAUGUUAAUACCAGAUUGCUGUUUACACUAAUUCCAUAUACAUGAUAAUACCACUAAUUUGGACUCUGCUAGUUCUUUUAUUUAAUAAGGCACCUCUAGGUCUGUACUUUGAGCCUUGAUCUGGGUACUUGGUACAGAGGGAGUGUCCUGGCCUGAAAGAAAGCCAGAUUAGGCUGCAGGAGUUCCUUUGAGGAGGUCUGUCUUUUAAUAACCCUGGCGGGUAAAUGAAUGGUAGGUAGCUGGUAGGUAGGCCUUCUUGUUCAUGUCUUUCUGUCUCCCCAAUCCACUCUUUGAAUUCAUGUUGAAUUCUUAACUUGAAAUUCUGUUGUUUUUUUUUUAAUUUUAGCUUUCUUUUUAUUAAACUAGUUAAUGUACAUAGUUUGAAAAAAUCAAAUAGAACUAAAAGGUUUAUAGUGAAAAAGUGUAGUUCCCUCUUCCCCAGUUUAGCAUUCCAAAGACAAACACUUGGAACUCUUAGUGGUUUGUGUUAGUAUUUACCUUCCUGUUUGAAAAUGUUAUACUACUUUUUGUUGACUUAUCAAUUUCAGAAACAGUUUCUCGAAUACCUUUUAUGGUAGACAGGAUUUACUUUACUUAAACUCUCCACCUCCCACAUUUUUCUUCCCCCACCCCUCCCAAAAUAGAUUUAUAUUCACACAACUUUUAGUUAGAACAAACUUUUUGUGAAAUAGAUAGACAUAAAUGUAGUUCACUGAUGUACCACAUGGUUAACUAUCAUUAUUUCCUUUUUACUAGAAUGUUAUUUUUUCUGGGGUUGGUAUUGCCUGAUUUUCAAAUUUGCUUAGUUUUUAAUGUACCUGUCACAAUGACUAUCCAAAGGCUUAAAUGCUGAAAAACAUCAGAUAAUCGUAUCAAUUCUCUUAAAAAAGUUUUUAAAAAUAUUUUGUCAUCCUUUAGGGACAUUUCUUCCACAGUCCUUCAUCUUCUGCCAUUUGUACUGUUGCCCUCCAGGCCUGUUCUAUGGUUCAGCAGUCAUUCUGAAACUCCCUUUAGUUUUUAGUCUCACAUUAGGUUUUUUUUUUUUUUUUUUUUUUUUUUUUUUUUUUUUGGCAAAGCUCCUCCACCAGUAACUUCCUAAGAAAAGGUGCAUAGAAAGUAAAGAUUUUAAGGCUUUACAGGUCUGAAAAUGUCUCUACUCUUGAUUGGUAGUUUGGAGUCUGGAAAAUAACAUGCCUUCAGAAUUUUAAGGGCAACAUUUCAUUGUCUUAAGGCAUUUAGUUUUUCUGUGAGAAUUCUGAUACCGUUCCUUUACCUGGGAUCUGUUUUUACACUCUGUAAGCUUUUAGGAACUUCUCAUUACUUCUGAUGUUUCAUAAUAAUAUGUGGGUCUUUAUUCAUUCAUCUUGAUGGCUACUUGACUUGGUGGAAUCUUUCAAUUUAGAGAUUUGUCUGCUUCAGUUCUGGGUGUGUGUGUGUGUGUGUGUGUGUGUGUGUGUGUGUGUGAUCUUUUUGACAGUUUUCUCUCUUCCAUUUUCUUUGUUCUAUCUUUCUAGAAUUUCUGUUAUUUGAAUGUUGGACCUCCCAGAGUUGGACCGCCUCUAAAUUUAAAAAGCUUUUUCUCUCUAGUUGUUCCUUAAGUUAUAUUAUCUUUGUUCUUUUUGUUAUCCUCCAGCUCUUCUGUUGAAUUUUCUUUAUAUAUAUAUUUUAAUUUCUAAGAGGUCUUUUUUUUCUGUUUCAUUUCAUAAAAACCUAUUUUUAUUUUAUAGAUUAACUGUUUCCCCAUAUCUCCCUGAGGAUAAAAUUAAGAUUUUUUUCUUACAUCUUUCCUGUUUCUUGAAUGGUUCUCCCCCUCCCCCACCAUGUUUCUGCUUUCUAUUUAUUUGUUUUGGGCUCUUUCAUUCUGAAGCCUUUCUUAGAAAUCAUCUAUUCAUAUUAGUCAUGUAUUAAAAAGCUAAUGUCAUAGGUCUUUAUAUGUGGGCAGGGUUUAUAAGUUGUCUAAAGGGCCAUCAGGUAGAGUUGGCCUUUUCUGUUGAGGUCCCCUAAAUUUCAGUGGAGGUCUUCUCUUUGGGGCCAGUUUCUCUAGAAAACUGGGUCCUGAUAGUAGGGUAAGAAAAGACAGCUGAGGACCCCAAGAUUUGUAUGAUGACUUUUACUUAAUCCCUCUAUCUUCAUCCUCUCUCAUGCCCAUCCGGCCCCACCCCCCAAAUCCUCCUCUGGCUGCUGACCCUCAGGUUCAGUUUUUCCUGUCAGUGGAGGUUGAGGGUGGGGCGUAGGCUGGCUGUGGAGAGUAGGGGAGAGGACCUGGGUUCCAGUUGCUCUUUAUACAGACUUCUAGUCCUGAUUUCAGCCCUAUACCUCACUCUCAUCUUCUACAAUACCUAGUGCUUCCAAGUCCUGAACUUAGUAGAGGUUUGGUGGGGUGUGUUUUUGGGCUUCUCCCUUUUGGGUACUUAGGCUUUAACUUCCUCCACUCUGCUAGGUUAGGUAUUGCACUUCCUCCUGGUUUUUAUCUGUAUAAACUUUGUUAAAAUCUCAUGGCUUUGUCGUCUGUGCUUUUUUGUGGAUUAAUACUAUUUAUAUUCCUUUAAUAUCUUUUGGUGGUUUGGAGGUAGAGGAAAUAAAUUCAUGUGGUUGGUUUGUAUGUUUCACUGAAAGUCUAGAUUUAAAUUCUAAUAGUGUAUAAAAAAUAAAAAUUCUUUAGUAUUAAUUUGUAAUUCAUUCUAGUGAUUUUUAAUUCAUAUGGUUUUACUGUACUACCUACCUCAUAGGGUUGUGAGGAUUAGAAGAAUCAAUUCAUAAAAAGCAGUUAGAAAAGUGCUGGGCACGUAGUGUGUUGAAUAAGUGUUAGUUAUUAAUAUUGUUUACUAUCAUUAUUAUUAUUACUACUAUCAGUUUUUUUUUUUUUUUCUGAGACAGGGUCUCACUCUUUCACCCAGUCUUGAGUAUAGUGGAGUGAUCUCAGCUCACUGCAGUCUCGACCUCCCAGGCUCAAAUGAUCCUUUUACCUCAGCCUCCCGAAUAACUAGGACUACAGGCAUGCACCACUACUCCUGGCUAAUUUUUGUAUUUUUUUGUAGCAGCAGGGUUUUGCCAUGCUGUUCAGACUGAUCUCAAACUCCUGGGCUCAAGGGAUCUGCCUGCCUUGACUUUCCAAAAUUCUCGGAUUACAGGCAUGAGCCACACUGCACUCUCCUAUCUCUCUCAAUUCAGUAACCUGUUUAUUCUUGAGUGAAAAUGUUUCACCAUAGGAAGAAUUACUAAUAUAUGGGAAAAUCUAGUGUUUGAUAAUGUUGACCCUACAUUUUUUUUGGACAGUCUCUGUCGCCCAGGCCGGAGUGCAGUGGCGCGAUCUUGGCUCACUGCAACUUCCACUUCCUGGGUUCAAGCAAUUCUCUUGUCUCAGCCUCCUAGGCUACAGGCUAGGACUACAGGUGCUCGCCACCAUGCCCAGCUAAUUUUUGUAUUUUUAAUAGAGAUGGGGUUUCAUCAUAUUAGUCAGGCUGGUCUUGAACUCCUGACCUCAGGUCAUCUACCUGCCUUGGCCUCCCAAAGUGUCGGGAUUACAGAUGUGAGCCACCGUGCCCAGCCGACCCUGCAUUUAACUAGACUUCAUAUGAAAUGUUCAGGUGUUAGGUGUUAUCUUUCUAAGAAACAUUCAAGCCUUAAGAAAUCCAAUCAGUUAUAGUUACUUUAAAAGUUUUAAAAAGAGUAUAACAAUUUUGAUGUGCUUUUAAGCUUUAUUGGUAUUAUAUUUUGUUUUUAUCAUAUAAAUAUGAAGUAUAGGAGAUAAGAUAAUGCAGAUGAUGUUUGUUAUGCCUUACCUACCGCCAGUAGAUGUAAUACUCUUAAUACAUGGAGUACAGAAAUAGUAGAUUCCCUUCAUUCCCAGUGCAACAGUGUUGGGAGGUGGGGCCUACCAGGAGGUGUUUAGGUCAUGUGGGUACCACCCUCAUGAAUAGAUUAAUGCCGCCGUGUAAAGGGCUUGUGGGCGUGGGUGAACACUCUCCUGCUCUUCUGCCAAAUGUCUCUCCCUUCCAAAGGACGUAGUGCUCUACAUAGUGUUGGAAGCGAGAGACUGAGCCCUAACAUGCCAGUGCCUUAUCUUGGAUUUCUCAGCCUCCAAAACUGUGAAAAAAUAAAUUUUCAUUCUUUAUGGUAAAUUCCCAUCACUGUAUCCAUAACCUCUUGUAAAUAGUUGUACACCUUUCAGAAAAUGUUGUGGACUUACAUAAGCAAAAUGCCUGCAUUUAUUUCAUAGGUAAAAUUUUAAUCUAUUUUCUAAUCAAAGUGUUUUGGGGAACAUUUAAUUUAAAUACUAUGUUCAAUUUUUUUAAUGGUCUGCUUCAGAUUUUUUUUAUAAGUUAAUGUUUUAAAACAAAAUAAUUGUGUUCUAGGUAGAAGCUACUCUGAGUUUAGGUUUUUAAAUCUCUUUCAGAUAUUUUAAGUAUCUUUUUUGUGUCUGGAUUCAGAGAGGUAUGAUAAUGAGAUUCUCUUCUAGAGGGGAAGUGGGAGUAGGUAACCAUACUACUCUUUCUACGGCUACAGAGCCGCAUACUCGAAGGAGGGAGAUUUUUAUUUGUAAGGACAUUUGUAUUAUCUUUCAUUAAAGUAGAGUCCCAUGGGCGUGGCAAAUGGCUGUAAAUAAAGUAAAAGUGGCUAAAGAAAACAGUGCCUGCUAUUAGCUUGAUGCUGGCAUUUUCUUCUUUCCCUGGAUGUGACUGUUAUUGUCUUUAUUGGGUCCCCUUAUUAUCUGCUUUGAUAUCCAUCUCUGGAACUUUGAUCUCUAAUUUUUUUUUUUUUUUUUUGAGACAGAGUCUCACUCUGUAGCCCAAGUUAGAGUGCAGUGACACGAUCUUGGCUCACUGCAACCUCCACCUCCGGGGCUCAAGCAAUUCUCGUGACUCAACAUCCCAAAUAGCUGGGACUGUAGGCACGCACCACCAUGCCCAGCUGAUGUUUUGUAUUUUUACAAAAAUUUUUCACCAUGUUGGCCAGGGUGGUCUCAAACUCCUAAGCUCAGGAGAUCCGCCUGCCUCAGCCUUUGAAAGUGCUGGGAUUACAGGCGGGAGCCACCGUGCCCGACCUGACCUCUCCAUCUUUGGCGUCCUUAUGCUGCCUCUUCUCCAAAUACAUGUUGGCCAGGGUGGUCUCAAACUCCUAAGCUCAGGAGAUCCGCCUGCCUCAGCCUCUGAAAGUGCUGGGAUUACAGGCGGGAGCCACCGUGCCUGACCUGACCUCUCCAUCUUUGGCGUCCUUAUGCUGCCUCUUCUCCAAAUACAGUAACUAAUCUAGUAUAUUUUCAUAGGAUAGAAUUUGCCCUUUCUGUCCCAUAAUAUGUUCCUCUUCCCCAAAAAGUUUUUUGUUGGUCUCUUUGGUAAUAAAACAUUUAGAGCAUUUACUGUGGGCCAGGUGCUUUACCUCAUGUUAGCCUUAUAACAGAGAUGCGGAAGUACAGGACUACCAGUGCAGCCAAGAUGCACAGCACCAGGAUUAACUCAUGAGACUGAUUAGAAUGAUGAAUAUCUUAUUGUAUCCUGAAACAUUAAGCCUUUAAGUUAUCCCUUUAUUUAGUAUUUAAAUUCACAUGCUUCUUGAUUUUUUUGGACUAGCAUUAGUUGUUGAAUAAAUAAAUAAUUCAGAAUGUAUCCACAAAACCUAGAAUAUAUGACAGGGUGGAUUCAGUUUUGCUUAGUUACUGUAGAUAAACCAAAUAAAUUAAUGUAAAGGGAUAUUAAUGCAUUAAGCAAUUUUUUUUGACAUAAAUGAAGGGUUGUUUCCAUGGGUAAUAUAUUCAGAAUAUUAAAGAUGAGUAAAAUGUAUGACUAUAAUGAAUUCCUUCUUCACUUUUACUCUGGCAAGGUGGGAGGAGGGUGCUGUUGAUAAUCUCUGUGCUUUUGCAAGUUUGGCACAAAGACUUUUACUCACUUAAAUCUCAAUAUAAAGUAUAUUGCCAGAUCUGGCAGCAUGGGGACAAUUAGGAACAAAGGAGAGAGAAUAGAAUCAGCCAUCAGGAGCUAUAACCACACUCUUCUUUCUCAACCUUUUCUGGUAUUAGUAGGCAGAACUCCUUUUGGAUGCGGUGAAGCAUUUUAUGAGUGAACAAUGGUGAGUCAUGUAAUGAAAGGAGAUGUUCUAGGAAAACUUUUCAGUCCCGCUCAGUGCUGCCAUCUUUUUCUCCCAGCACUCUGGACUUAAAAUUCUGAGAGAACAGGGUAUUUCCCACCCUUCCUCUUACUUUUUGAAAGCAAUACCUGAGUUAUUAAGCAAUCAUUUAGACAGUAUGAAUAAACCAAAAUUCACCUUGACACUCCAUCCCCUAGAGGUAACCAUUCUUUUCUAGUAUAUAUUCUUCCAGACCUUUUUCCUGUGUAUUGACUUUUAAAUAGAUGUACAUUGCAAUAGUUUGGAUUAGCUCAUCCAUAGCAGGGUGGUUAAAUAAACAGUGGCACUUUUUUUUUUUUGAGACAGAGUCUCACCCUGUCGCCCAGGCUGGAGUGCAAUGGCGCGAUCUCGGCUCACUGCAACCUUUGCUUUCCAGGUUCAAGCGAUUCUCCUGCCUCAGCCUCCCAAGUAGCUGGAAUUACAGGCGAGCACCACCAUGCCUGGCUAAUUUUUGUAUUUUUGGUAGAGACGGGGUUUUACCGUGUUGGUCAGGCUGGUCUCGAAUGCCUGACCUUGUGAUCUGCCUGCCUUGGCCUCCCAGUGUCAGGAUCCUGGCCCCAGUGGCACAUUUUUAUGAUGCAUCUGGUACUAAAGAAGGAGCUGGCUUUAUGACCUUUACUUGAGUAUUUUUUUGUGUGUGACAGUUGAACAAUUCUGACCCCUAUUAUUGUUGGCUGGACAGGCAUUUUCUUUUUAAUUCCUCUAUGCAAGGAACUGUGGAUUGCUUUUUUCUGGAUAGCUAGAACGAGGCCAUUUUCUUUCAAAAGACAGUCCUAGAGUUUCCAGUGGUUUUCUUUAAUUGUGUAUGCGUGAGUGUGACAGUGUGUGUGCCUGUGUCUCUAUCUGUGCAUGCAUCUGUAUGCACAGUUUCUUAGUUGUGGACAAUGCAACUUGGAAUCAUUUUAGUUUUCCAAUUGAUUUUAAAAGUUUAUCUAUAGAAGAUGAGACAAAUUUGCUGUAGAAGUUACCACUACUUGGUCAAAAUAGAGAGUUGUGGGUUUUUUUUUUUGUUUGACAACAAUCAAAAGUAUGGCCUACAGAUAGUAAGGGUUAACCACCCAGAUUUUUGUCAGAUAAUAUAUACAUGUCCAUGUAAUUAAAAGUCUUCAUUUGACAAAUUUAUAUGGUAAAUGAGCAUAAAAUGAAUAUCUUUUCAGUAUUAGAACAUUUCUGUUUAUGCCCUAUUCCAGUGGUAUUUGUGGUCGCUAGGGGUUGCUGGGUUAUCCAAGUGAUUCAGCAUGCCUUCAGAAUUGGCAUCCUCGGGUGAUUGUCCAUAGCCUCUUGCAAUGGUGCCUCAUCUUGGGGAGGCUUUAGAACACAGCUCUCAUUUAGCUUAUUAUUGAUUUUUUUUUCUUGUUUUGCAGUUGUUGGCUAGAGAAAAGUGUGUAGCAAUAAGUACGCACACUUACUGUGGUUUACCAUCAUGACCAUGGAUAGCAAACUGCCUUUUUUUUUUUUUUUAACUCCUGUGUCAUCUCUGAUGUUGUGGCUAAUUUUAAGACUUUGAUUUUUCAGCUAGGAUUAGCGGAGAAUGACCUACCUACUUGAUUAAUGAUGUCUGCAUGGGCUUACUAAGAGGGUGUGGGGAAUGGUGGCAGGGGUAACUAUCAUCGAGAAUAUAGGGCAAUGGGUAUAUUCUAACUUUGCAUAACUUUGCUAGAUUAUAUAUAUCUUUACUCACAAUAAGCAAAGUUGAACAACUUAAAAUUGAUUCCCUGUUUUCUGUUUUCACUAUCCAACUAGGAUGAACUCUUAAGUUCAUACAUAUACUUUAAAAUGGGAACAAACAUAGCCUGUCAUGUCUUUAUUUAGGCUAAGUGCAUAUGUAUGUAUAAGUAAUGUGUAUAUCCUUCACUUAUUAAUAGUGCCUUCAUGAAUUCAAAGACCCUUGUCACAUGGUGCUCAGGAAAAAAAAAGUGCCAAUAUUCUUUUUUUUUUUUUCUCUAAGAAGUACUAGUUUAGGUAAGUGAAAUUCAAUAGCAUAUCAGUGCUUUACCUUAGUCACUUUUUGUGUUUUGAUCACCCUUAGUCAUCACUGGAGAGAAGAGUUUGAAUUCAUUUGUGGUUUUGCUUUAGUGGCAAACCUCCUUACAGGGAUGAGUUGCCCUCCAUUCUCCUUGCCAUAUUUGGUUAAUCUAGGCCAUGACCUUUGAGGGGAAAAGGCACAGAUUGCAACUUUUCUUUCCUGCUUUUGUGAAUCAGGCCAUGUUCACGCAGGGUCCUUGAAGGUGACUUGAGUGAGGAAGCUAUAUACCGAUGACUUACCAAUUUUUGGUCUUAUAACAUUCUCUCUCUUUUUUUUUUUUUUUUUUUGUAGCAUAUGGCUUCCUCUACUGUAUGUUGGCAUUUGCCACUUUUGGGGAUUUGACUCCUGCAGGUAUUUUUUUUUUUUUCUUUUGGGGGAGUGUGACGGCAGUGGAUAUAGUCUUAGAUGAUGUUUUUAAUAGUUCAAGUCCAUUAGUGUCUUACUCUAGAGAAAACGAAAGACUCACUGUGUGAGUUUUCUUGCCCUCUGGUUUUCAGAAUUCUGUGUAGUUUCUCAACAUUUCCUUUCUACCUGUCCUGAAGAGCUCUUAUGGAAAUCAUGGUUGAAUGUUAGUAAAUUUCUAAGAGCUUUCCAAUGUUGUCUAUAAUUAGCCAAAAAAAGACAUAUGAACUUUUCUCAUUCUGUCUACCUUUUUAAAAUUUUAUUCACUUUAUCUUUUUCUCCAGUUUUGAUAGAUGAUUAUAGAGUUCCCCAAAAUGGCCUUCUUACUAUUUCUAUAUUAGGUAUAUUAUUUCAGAAAAGAAAAUAAUCACUUGGGAAUGGCGGUGAGUUCAGGGGGUCUGUUAACCAUUUAAUUUAGGAUUGUUUAUACAUUUAUUUACCUCUUUUAAAAAAUUUCUUCAGUUAAUAUUCAUUGACCACUCACUAAGUGUUAUGUUGCUAGUAUUUAUCUUUGCUUUCUAAUUAUUUUUUUGUAAUUUUUUUGCUUUCUAAUUCUUGAGUGAAUUUAAAACUCACUGCUUUAUUAUUUAAUAUCUUAGAUACAAUGACUAUCUUAAUUAUAAUUGGCUUUCCAAAAUUUUCACUUUUUUUCAGUUAACUAGUUGAAUAGUAUUUAUCAUUCACAUUUGCACCCUAACUAUUGUUUUAACCUAAACAUAAAUAAGCAAGCAUUAGAAAGUAGCAUAAUUGCUGUUAAAAUAGUCUUUUCUUUGCGUGUUUAAAUAUUGUUAGAAACAUAAGCACAUGAAUUUUUUUGGCCUUUUAAAUGUCUUUAUUGUAGCUAGUUAUAAGAUGUAUAUAUAGCUUAUAUAUGUGUAUAUACACAUACAUAUAUAUAUAUACAUACAUAUAUAUACAUAAAAUGAUUCUUGCAAAAGUAGUUAUGGGUAUUUAAGUGAAAAAUUUGUAAGUUUAGAAGUUAAGAAAUUGGAAAUAAUGGAAUUGGUUUAAAAAGCUAGUCUCUAAAUUAACUUAGAAACCUAAUAGCAAAUACAGAUUUUGAUUGCUAUAACUAAACACUUUAAUUUUGAAAAAGUUUCAGAAUAGAAUUUCUAUUCCCAGGGGAAAAUAAACUUCAUUUAAAAAUAUAUGUAUACUUAUUUUGUGAGUAUUUUUUUCUUUUCCAAAUUCCAAAAGGUGUAUACUCUAUAUUUUUGUCAUAAAAAUUCUGCUUGUCGAAAAUAUUGUAGUAAUUUUAUAAAUUCAAUAAAACCUGAGUGAUGUGAA